AGUGGGCACAUGGGGGUGCGGGGGUGUAGGUGCCAAGCGCCAUGGCUUAGACCCGAGAUUGGAGUCCGGCCGCCCCCCGACAGCAGCCGCCUCCUGCCCCCCGUGCGCCCUAGGCGCCACCAUGUCGGGAGACAAACUUCUGAGCGAACUCGGUUAUAAGCUGGGCCGCACAAUUGGAGAGGGCAGCUACUCCAAGGUGAAGGUGGCCACAUCCAAGAAGUACAAGGGUACCGUGGCCAUCAAGGUGGUGGACCGGCGGCGAGCGCCCCCGGACUUCGUCAACAAGUUCCUGCCGCGAGAGCUGUCCAUCCUGCGGGGCGUGCGACACCCGCACAUCGUGCACGUCUUCGAGUUCAUCGAGGUGUGCAACGGGAAACUGUACAUCGUGAUGGAAGCGGCCGCCACCGACCUGCUGCAAGCCGUGCAGCGCAACGGGCGCAUCCCCGGAGUUCAGGCGCGCGACCUCUUUGCGCAGAUCGCCGGCGCCGUGCGCUACCUGCACGAUCAUCACCUGGUGCACCGCGACCUCAAGUGCGAAAACGUGCUGCUGAGCCCGGACGAGCGCCGCGUCAAGCUCACCGACUUCGGCUUCGGCCGCCAGGCCCAUGGCUACCCAGACCUGAGCACCACCUACUGCGGCUCAGCCGCCUACGCGUCACCCGAGGUGCUCCUGGGCAUCCCCUACGACCCCAAGAAGUACGAUGUGUGGAGCAUGGGCGUCGUGCUCUACGUCAUGGUCACCGGGUGCAUGCCCUUCGACGACUCGGACAUCGCCGGCCUGCCCCGGCGCCAGAAACGCGGCGUGCUCUAUCCCGAAGGCCUCGAGCUGUCCGAGCGCUGCAAGGCCCUGAUCGCCGAGCUGCUGCAGUUCAGCCCGUCCGCCAGGCCCUCCGCGGGCCAGGUAGCGCGCAACUGCUGGCUGCGCGCCGGGGACUCCGGCUAGAAGCCGGGUGGUUCCAGCCAUUCCUGCAGCCAAGGGCACUGGGCCAGGGCGGCGCACGCGCAAGAGGCGCGCUUCGAGGGAAUAUGCGAAGCUGCCGCGUGCUGCUGCACAUGCGCUUUUUCCCUUCCGCUUCCCUCCCUUUCUUCCCACGGGGGAGUCCGCAGUUGCCCUUGUUCGGAAUCCACGUUCCCCGCGAUCCCGGGAGCUGGAGGCGCAUGCGCAUCCGCGAUUCCCUGCGACCAGGCCCCGAGAGGGCGAGACCAGAGGGGACGGAAGCAUUGCGCCUGCGCGGAACUCUCAGCCUCUGCGCGGAGGGCGUCCCUUCCCAACCAGCCGUGGGUGCCAGGUUCCCGGUUGGAACCUGCAAUAAACUCGCUGUUCCUCGCA